CAAAUAUUGAAUCACAGCUAAAUGGAAACCAGAUGUGGCACUCAUCAAGUUUAUAUUUUUGAAUCAGGGAGAAGAUAAAGACAUUUGCAGUUGCAACUUGGAGGCUACAGCCACAUUGUUAGAUUAGGGCAUUUUUCAAUUUUAUCUGAUAUGUUCAGGUAAACCAAGGCUCCUUCUCAAAGAAACAGAAGUUUGAAAUUUUGAAUGACUGGAGUUGCUCAAUGGCCCAGUUCAACAAAAAUCAGCUCAUAGCAUGCAGAAGAAAUGGAACGACCACAAGUGAUUUUAACCAAACUGAAGUUGCUGAAUUUUUCCUCAUGGGAUUUUCGAAUUCCUGGGAUAUUCAGAUUGUACAUGCUGCUCUAUUCUUCCUAGUUUACCUGGCAGCUGUCAUAGGAAAUCUCCUAAUCAUCAUACUUACCACUCUGGAUGUUCACCUCCAAACCCCAAUGUAUUUCUUUUUGAGAAACUUGUCUUUCUUAGAUUUUUGUUACAUCUCUGUCACAAUUCCAAAAUCUAUUGUUAGUUCCUUGACUCAUGAUACUUCCAUUUCUUUCUUUGGGUGUGCUCUGCAAGCCUUCUUUUUCAUGGACUUGGCAACUACGGAGGUAGCCAUCCUUACAGUGAUGUCCUAUGACCGCUAUAUGGCCAUCUGCCGGCCUUUACAUUAUGAGGUCAUCAUAAACCAAGGUGUCUGUCUGAGGAUGAUGGCCAUGUCGUGGCUCAGUGGGGUGAUCUGUGGAUUCAUGCAUGUGAUAGCAACAUUCUCAUUACCAUUCUGUGGGCGCAAUAGAAUACGUCAAUUUUUCUGUAAUAUUCCACAGCUCCUAAGCCUCUUAGACCCCAAAGUAAUUACCAUUGAGAUUGGAGUCAUGGUUUUUGGUACAAGUCUUGUGAUAAUCUCCUUUGUUGUAAUUACUCUCUCCUACAUGUACAUUUUUUCUGUCAUCAUGAGGAUUCCUUCUAAGGAGGGUAGAUCAAAAACAUUUUCUACCUGCAUUCCACAUCUUGUGGUUGUAACACUCUUUAUGAUAUCUGGCAGCAUUGCCUAUGUGAAGCCAAUUUCAAAUUCUCCCCCCGUUCUGGAUGUUUUCCUGUCUGCGUUCUACACAGUCGUGCCCCCGACCCUGAACCCCGUCAUCUAUAGUCUGAGGAAUAGGGACAUGAAGGCAGCCCUGAGAAGGCAGUGUGGUCCCUGAGAAGGCAGUGUGGUAUGCUAGAUGAAGAAUUUGAUUACGGACCAGACUCUUGAACUCUUGCUCUAAUCAGGCAAUUUGUAAACUCUCUGGGUUUAUAUUUUCAAUUGAUUGCUGAGCUCUUUCUUGAUUUUUAAAUUAAAUUCAGCUAUAGUUUACCAUACUAACCAUAUUUGGGUGAAUUCAACCUUAGAAUGCACUAAAAGGUACUUCGGGGUGUUCAAAACAUUAGAACUUGUGCUUUUAUUCAUUUUUAUGAGUUGUAGAUCUCAAAAUUUUAUAAAUUAUAUUGUACUCAGUAAUACAACAUAUUAAUUAAUAUAAAAGUGAAUUACUAAUAUAAAUGAAUUACUACCGUAUGUGUAUAUUAAUUACAGCAGAACAAGAUCAUAUGGAUUAAAAACAACCAAAUGGAAAAUAAACAUAAGGUAACAGUGUGUGCUCAGAAUUUCUUCAGCAUUAUAAAGGAUGGUCAAAUAGGCUAGAGACCAGUGUUCUGGGAGCAUAUCUAUUGGGUGAGAUGAAAUAUAUGCAAUAAUAUCACAAACUAUAAAGGUUCACAUAUGUUUAUGGUGCUGUGUAUAGGAAGGUUCACAGAGGAGAAAUGUCAUUUUCAUUAAACACAAUAUUAUGUUAAGCUAACUAAAAUCUUCUUCCAUUUUUCCUCUGCAUAGGAAAGUAUGAACUGAAAGUUAUUAUGCAUUAUUCCCAGAGUGCUUUUAUGUGUAUUCUAUCUAUAUAAAUAUUCAUCUAUAAAAUGCAUAGCAUCAUUUUAUAAAUUAAUACUUAAACUAUAAUAUAAAUAGCAUCCUACCUUAGUUAUCCUUUUUAAAGUCCUUUAAAUUGUAUUUUUAGUUGACAAAUAAAAAUAAUUAUAUAUGCCUAUGGGGUAAAAGUGAUGUUUUAAUACAUGUUUGCAAUGUGGAAUGAUUAAAUCAGGCAAUGUAAUAUAUCACCUGAAACAUUUGUCAUUCAUUUGUGGUGACAUUGUUUAAAAUCCUCUUUUAACUGUUUUGAAACACACAAUACAUUGGUAUGAACUAGAUUAAUCUUGCUGUGCAAUAGAUCACCAGAGCUUAUCCUUCCUGUCUAACUGGAACUCUGUGCUCUCCGACCAACAUUUCCCCUUUACCAGUCUACCAUCACCCUUGCCUCCAUCUUCUGGUCAGCACCAUUCUACUCUGUAUUUUUAUGAGUUUGACUUUUUCAGAUUCCACAUAUAAGUGAGAUCCUGUGGUAUUUGUCUCUCUGUGACUGGCUUAUUUCACGUAACAUGAUGUCUUCUCUAGGUUCAUCCAUAUUGUCACCAAUGACAGAAUUUCAUGUUUUUUUUCAAGGCUGAAUAGUAUUCCAUUGUGUGUGUAUACUACAUUUUAAAAAUCCAUUUGUCCAUGGUGGACACUUAGAUUGAUUCCAUAUUUCGGCUAUUGUAAUGCCGCAAUGCACAUGGAAAUACAGACAUGCCUUUGACCUACUGAUUCCAGUUCUUUGGAUAGAUGCAAGCGUACCUCAUUGUAUUGCACUUCAUUUGCUGAAUUUCACAAAUAUUGCAUUUUUUAUAAAUCAAAGGUUUUUGGUAACUUUGCAUUGGGCAAGUCUAUUGGCACCAUUUUUCUGACAGCGUGUGCUCACUUCACGUCUGUGUGUCACCUUUUAGUGAUUCUCACAAUAUUUCAAACUUUUUCAUUAUUGUUAUGUCUGUUUUGGUGAUCUGUGAUCAGUGAUGUUCAAUGUUACUAUUGUAUUUGUUUCGGGGAGCCAUGAACUGUUCUCAUAUAAGAUGAUAAACUUAAUAAGUGUGUGUGUUCUGACU